AUCGUGUCUGAAAAACAAAUUAACAAACUGUUAAAUUCUGCACACUGCUCAUCAAGCAUGUAUCGGCAAAACCUUUCAUAAUAAUUAUUUAAUAAAGAUAAAUAUAACAUUAAUUUGAUGCUUUUGUUUUGGGGGAUGCAGACUUUUAAAAAAAAACAACAGCAAGAUACAGAAAGGUGUACAUCAAGAGAUGAACUCUCCUGUAUCAGACAGUCAUAUCAAGUUUUACAGGAGCUUAUUACAUCACCUUAAAAUAAUGUUCUUUAACGGAGUUAAAAAGGGGAGAAAACCUGUUCAAGAAUGCCGCCCGGCCAAAUGGCCCAUGAUUGAUGGGGCAGCAACAACCAGGGGGUAUUUGCCAGUUCACCAGUGCCAAGUCCUCAGAGUGAGUUUGCUGCUUGUGACAGCUGGUGUUCUCUACUGGAAGGCUGUUUCUGUAUACAUCUAUGAUUUGCAUAUUUAUAUACCUCGGCUGCUGUAUGAGGUCCACAUUUCACAGCAGUGUGUAUAAGCUGUGCAGCCUUACUGCUUGAGUGCCUCUAGGCAUGAGAUGGUAGAAUUGGUUUGAGUAAAAUGAGAAUUUUAGGUUUUUGUGUUUUGCAGAGUAGCCAGUAAUGCCACAUUUUUGUUCAUCUCUCUCUUCAUCAACUUCAGUAAUAUUUUUGAGUCAUCUAUAUGCAUGGGCUACCAUUUGAAGCAGACACAUUAUAUGCUCUCUAGGAGGGUACAAGCUCAGACACUAAGGCAUCAUAGGAAUAUAGAAAGGAAGACAUUAAAGGAAUAUAUUUAGUCAAGUUGAAGCCUGAAGUGAGGAUUGUGGGAUUUGCACAUUGAAGGGAGUUACUGAUGUUUUUCCUUAAGUUGGGGAGAACUUAAGAAGGUAAGAACUGCUCUGCUAAGUCAGAUAAAUGAACUUCUAAGCUGAGGCUUCUCUUUCUAAAUAGUAAUAUCACAGGGAUUCUGUAACAAAUGAGAUUUCCACAGUUGUUUGAAAUAUCAAAUAUAGAAUACUUAUUUGCAAAAAAAAAUGGGGGCAGGCACAUUGGAUAAAAAGAACAUGAAGAAUGUAGCUUAAAGGAAAUAGGAGUUGGAUAAAUAAACAAUAAAUAUUUGGAAAUAAAGUGGUCUUAGGAACAGUGACAGUGGUUGGUGAACAGGAAGAGAUCUAUUAGGGUGGAGCUAUCAUAUAAAGAACUUAGAGGUGGUUGAGAAUCUUAGCCUUUAUUUGCUGUGAGAUUGCAAAUUUCUUAAGGUCAACUGAGGAUGUUAAUUUAGUAAAUAUGAUGGGUGGGGUCUUCAAAUGGAAAACAUAAUCUGAAGCAAGAUGUUUGCAAAGGCAGUUUCCAGAAAGUGGCGGUAUCAGAAAAAAAGGUAACCAGGUUAGAAUUCUAAUGAGUGAAGAGGAUGGGGUAAUUUUUCAACAAAUGAAGACAAUAAUAUCUGACAGAAAUAUUUCAGUUUUGUGUGAAGAACAAUAAAGAGUUUACAAGUGAAGUGAAGACAUCUUCUGUACCUCAUUAUUCUGUCAUGACCUGGAGCAUCAGGUGGUUGCUGAUGCAGCAGCUCCUAUCCUGAAGAACAUUCUUGUCAUAGACUGAAUGUUUAUGUCCUUGCUAAAUUCAGUUUAGAACUUUAUCCCAGUGUGAUACUAUUUGGAAAUGUGGUAUUUGGGAAGUGAUUAGGCUCGACCCUCACUUAUGGGAUUAGUGCCUCUGUAAAAUAGGCCCCAGAGAGGUCCCUUUCCCCUUCCAUACUCUGUGAGGACAAAGUGAAAAGUCAGCCAUCUAUGAACCAGGAAGUGGGUCCUCAUCAGACACCAAACCUGUUGGCACCUUGAUCUUUGACUUCUCGGUCUCCAGAAUUGUGAGAAAUAAGUUUCUGUUGUAUAAGUCACUGUCUAUGGUAUUUUGUUAUAGCAGCCUGCAUAAAGACACUACUGUAUGUUCCAAACACUCAUAUUCAUUAUCUAUAAACCUUAUAUAAACACAUGAGUGUAUAUUAUCAUCCCUAGUAUAGAUAAAAUAAUGGAAACAGAAAAUAAUAAAUAACUAUCCAAGUUCAUACAACUGAUAUGUGCCAGUGUCAUGAUUUGAGCUCAGGUCUGUUGGAUUCCACAAGUUAUUUUAGUUUAUUUGCUUGUUUGCCCGUUUUGCUAACAUGCUGCUUCCUUAGACAGAGGAGGAAUAUAAACAAAAGGUAGUAAACAGUUCUCUUGGGCAUAUUUAAUUUGAGUUGGCAAGGAAAUAGCCAUCUGGAGAAACUGCUGAGACAAAAUACUUGCUGGGUUUGCUCCAUGCAUACCUGUGAAAUGUGUGGUGUUAGAUAUUACAGUCCCUAUUUUAUAAUUUAAGAUCUUAAGAAAUGGAGUGGAUUAUGAUAACAAAACUAGUUUAUGCUAAAAGUGCAGAAAGUAAAGAUGAUCCACAUGACUAGUCUGUAUUUAUUCCAAGUAUAGCCCUCUAGUACAGUACAGAUCACUGGAAAAGCAUUUUGAGUGUCUAGACAGCAAACAAUAAUUUUUCACAGAUAUCAACCAAAUAUAAAAACUAAAAUAUUAUAUAUAGCUGCAAAAAACUAGACAUUGUCUUUGAGGCAUUACUGUCUGAUGAAAUGAUAAAUAUCAUGAAUGAUAUAUAAAUCUAACUGUUUUAAAAUUACCCAUUUCUCUUCUUAUUUCACUUGGCAUAAGCAUGGUUCAGACCCACCUUCAGCAUACUGCUCAUACAGUCGGAGUAAACAGCUAUUCGUAGAACCCUUUGCUAGCUCAGUCACAAAUCCAAACUAAACGUUAUCCAUAUGUUUACAGGAGACUUUUUUUGGGAUAUGUUGUCUUCUAAGUAAUAUUUGACAAAGUGGCUACUGUUAAAUUCCAUUCACAUGCAUCAGGUAAAUGUCCAUCUGACAAAAUCAAUUCAUACAUGGUAAAUAAUUUUAAAAAUAUGAUUAUUAUUAUUUUAUAUUGCAUUGAACUUCACAUUUAGAGCUUCAGACUAUGGACUUGCCAAAAUGCCAUAUCUAGCCUUAAUGUUUAGUACGUAGUGGCUUAAGACCAUAGGUUCUAAGGUCAGACCAUAUGAAUUACAUUCCAGUCUGACUCAUUUACUAGUUGUGUGAUACCAUGCAAGUUAUAUUACCUUUUGUGCUGGAGUUUCCUUUUCUAUAAAGAAUGCAACAAUAACAAUCAUAGUUGUUUGUAUGUCUCUGUGUGUGUAUGUAACCAUUAAGAGAAACUGUAAUCUAAAGUCUUUACCAGACUGCCUGAUAUAGUAGGUGCUCAAUUUUUUAUUAGGUAUUAUUGUUGUUUUCAUUUUAAUUGUAUCUGUUAAUACUUUAAAAACAUGUUAGUCACAUAUGGGCUAUGCUUUACUGCUUUUUCACACUAAGAAAAUUAUUUUCAAUAACUCAUCAGACUGACUUUUUUUUUUUUUUUUUUGAGACGGAGUCUCGCUCUGGAAUGCAGUGGUGCGAUCUUGGCUUACUGCAACUUCUGCUUCCCAGGUUCAAGUGAUUCUCCUGCCUCAGCCUCCCGAGUAGCUGGGAUUACAGGCAUCCACCACUAUGCUUGUAUUUUUAGUAGAGACGGGGUUUCACCAUGUUGGUCAGGCUGGUCUCGAACUCCUGACCUUAGGUGAUAUGCCUGCCUUGGCCUCCUAAAAUGUUGGGAUUACAGGCGUGAGCCACCAUGCCUGGCCUCAGACUGACUUUCCAUAGAGAAGAAAAACGGUACAAAAUCAUUUUCUGUGUUUCUGAAAGCUUUUAUAUUUAUCUUGCAUAGGAAACUCCAAAUGCUUAUGAUGUUAAAGAGGAAGAGGUUAUACCUUUGAAGACUAUUAAUAAGAUUUGCUCUAGUAAAUUACUGAGUUUCAUUAGAACUCUCUUCUGAGACCAAACCCCUAAAAGGGGAAAAUAAUCUAUUAAUUCAUUACUCUAUGUUACCACCCACUUUAUCGUGUUUAUUCAGAAUUUGGACAAAAGACAACAAAAAGAAAAGCAAGUAACAGUGGUUUAAAGUAUGCUCAAAAUGAAGAGAAAAAAUUAGAUGUUGGAAGGAAACUGGUUUAGACGCAACAUAAUAGAUUUGAUAGGGUUCCAUGCUUUUUGAAGAUUUGGUUUUUUUGUAGUUUUUUUUGCAAUAGAUACCUACUUUACAGUCUAUACUAAACUUAAUCUUUAUUUUUGAUAAACUGUCAUUAUUUUAAAAUGUUUUAUUUCCUAGUUUAUUUUUAUUUCAUAAUAAUUUCUAAUAAUCUUUGUACCUCAUCAUGAUCAAGUAGUUAACAAUUUUAAAUACACAUAAAUGCCUUGGAACAGUUUUCAGUAUUCAAAAUUAUAUUGGUAAAUAUCUCUCAAAAUGAAACAUUUAUUCUUAACUUUUAAUGUAACAACAUUCUCCAAUUUAUUUGUUUUGCAUUCAUGUUUUCAAUGCAACGUUGGGCUUUCUGAAAGUAGGAUAUACAGCUAUUCUGUUUAUUUUUCCUGUAGGACUGAUAAGCCUAUUCUUGGAAUCAUAAUAUAAAUUGAGGUGCCUUUGACAAUGGAUGAGAAUAAAUCUCUUUUUCCCAUUAGUAACAAAAGGCUUAGGCUGGAUUUUGUUCUUCAGGGUGUACCAACAAGCUUAACUGUUAAAGUACUAUAAGAAUUGUAUUGUGUGUAAUUCAGAAGGAGUUCUAAAAACUGUAGCAAUUUCUAUUGUAAAAUAUUUAAUGAGGUUUGUCAAAUGCAAAGAUCAAGACACCAUAAAUAGAUAUCCAGAUUUGGUCUUCAAAUUAAAUUAGAUAAGAAAAUUUACUCUCCCUGAAUCCAAGGUAUUUAUGUAUAGACACACACAGACACACACACACACACAAUAUGUAUGUACAUAAGGAGUGGUAAUAUAUAAUAAAACCAAUUUAUAAGCAGUAUAAGAAUUGUUUAUAAAAUUCAAAUAAGUUUAAUUCCUCAAAAUAAUUCACACGACUUGAAUGGAAUACUCUUCUCAUGUUGUAGUCCUUUCACCCUUCUGGAGAAUUUCUCAUUUACUGAUAAAUUUAUGAACAAUAAGAAAUACAGUUUUACAGUUUUAUGAAAGUUUGUUUCACUGAACACAGUGUUACCCAACUUAAUUACACAAUUUAAUUAUUAAUAUCUGGAGUUGGGCUCUGUGAGUAAAUAUUUGUUGUGUUGGUACCAAGAUAUCAAGGUCUUUGAAGUCAAUUUCAGAAAUAAAUUCCAGGAAUAAUUUGAACAAUAAUUACAUUAUUGAAAUAAGAACAUAUUUUUGAAAAAUAAAUUUUCUGAAAAGCUCGCAGAAGACUGUUACAUAACUGGCACAGAUCCCGUCUAUGUCUGAAGAAGGAAAAGAAAGGGAGAGAGAGAGAGAGACCCUCCUGCACUUUGGAUUUCACACUGAGUAUAUACUUUUUAAUUUUUAAUUUUUUUUUGAGAGGGAGUCUCGCUCUGUCGCCCAAGUUGGAGUGCAGUGGCACAAUCCCGGCUCACCGCAACCUCCGCCUCCUGAGUUCAAGCGAUUCUCGAUUCUCCUGCCUCAGCCUCCUGAGUAGCUGGGAUUACAGUUGUGCACCACCACGCCCGGCUAAUUUUUGUAUCUUCAGUAGAGACAGGGUUUUACCAUGUUGGCCAAGCUGGUCUCGAACUCUUGACCUCAAGUGAUCUGCCUGCCUUGGUGUCCCAAAGUGCUGGGAUUACAGGCAUAGGCCACCAUGCCCGGCCUGGAUUUCACACUGAGUAUAAAUCAGUGGCCAUCUAUCAUUAAGGGGAGGGCAGGAGAGCUGAGACCCAGUAAAGUAAUGAAGCUGAUUCCAUUUCAUUGGCUUAUUAGUACUUAUUUUGUUUUUAUUUUAUAAGUAGUUUAUGAACAUGUUUUUUAAAUAUAAAAUAUUCAAACACCACAGAUAGAUUGGAAGCUCCAUUUUCCACAAUUUCUAGUCCAAUUCCUCAGGAAAAAAAUGUUGUAAUUAUUUGGAGUAAGUGCCCCUAUUUCACAGAGUCACAUUGUCUUUCAAGAAGAACAAAUAAAAUAGAUUAUGGAAAUAGCAAUAAUAUCCUUGAAUUCCUUCUACUUAUACCUUGCUGCCUAAAAAUUACUAACGAUUUAUACAUUCAACGAAUGUUUGUUUAAUAUCUAUUUGCCUCCUAGAUGCUGGGGAUAGAGCAGUGAAUAUAAAUAAUUAAGAUAACAUAACAAAAAAACAAAAACUGUCCCUUUAUGAAGCUUAGAUUCCAGACCAGGAGGUAAUUAAUAAAGAAGAUAAACAAAAAUCCACAAUAUAUCUGAUGGUGAUAGGUGAUAGUGCUAUGGAGAAAAGGAAGGAAGGAGAAUACUGGAGGUGUUGGAACUUAGGGGCAGGGGCUGCUGCAAUCUUCAAUGGUGUGACAUAGAAAUCCUCCCUGGUAAGGUGACAUUUGAGUAAAGACCUGAAGGAAGUGAAGAUGAACACAAUUUGCUUACCACCACCACCACCUACCAUGCCUCUCACCACAUCUGAUUGGGCUGUAUCACCAUGCCCAUGCAUGGAGGAUAAUUAAGGCCCGGCCAUGACAGGCUAUUCCCUCAGCCCCCUAAGGAGAAAGAACCUAAGCAGCUUUUCAUAGUUAAUUGCUUAAAUUUAUUUAAAAUCAUAUUCCAUUAAGUGAAUUAUGGACAGUUCUCUUUCCUGUGUGGUAUGCCAGAAAGAGCAUGAGCUUUGGAGCAGAGAGACCUGGAUUCAAAUGCUGACUCUGCUAAUGACUAGCUAUUUACUUGAUACAGAAAAGCUUCUGUUUGCUUAUUUGCAAAAUAAAAAUAUUAAUAUUAAAAUAUUGUGAGAAUUGAACAGGUGCUACUAAAUGAAAUGUGAUUAAAGUAUGUUAGAUGUCCCAGCGGUCUCCUAGUCCCUGAUUCCAUUCUAUAUGUUUACAUUUCCCUGGCAACUUGAGGAUGAUAUUCUCAUGUCUUCUGAUAGAUUUCUGUCUACUAGAAAGUAAACUGCAAAAUGUUAAAAAUUAAUUUUAUUUAUUUAUAUUUAUUUUAUUUUAUUUUAUUUUAUUUAUUUCUCAUUGUGGUAUUUUAUUUUUUAUUUGAGUAUCUCUCAAAGUCAAGUUCCUCAGGUAUUGUAGGUGCAAAAUUUUGCGAAAUGAAUGAAUAUGUUUUUGUGGGUUUUUGUUCUUGUUGUUGUUGUUUUGUUUGUUUGUUUUUUGAGAUGGAGUUUCACUCUUGUUGCCCAGGCUGGAGUACGAUGGCACUAUCUCAGCUCACUGCAACCUCUGCCUCCCAGAUUCAAGCGAUUCUCCUGCCUCAGCCUCCCAAGGAGCUGGGAUUACAGGCAUGUGCCACCAUGUCCGGCUAAUUUUGUAUUUUUAGUAGAGAUGGGGUUUCUCCAUGUUGGUCAGGCUGGUCUCGAACUCCCGACCUCAGAUGAUCCACCCGCCUCAGCCUCCCAAAGUGUUGGGAUUACAGGCGUGAGCCACGGCACCCAGACAAAUGAAUACAUUUUAUGUCUAUGUGUGUGUGUGUGUGUGUUUUAAAAGUAAUCCCUCCUUUUUAGAGAUUCCAUCUCAGAUUUUGAAACUACCUAUUCAUUAGCACUUGGGUUUUCUUAGCUAUAAAAUUUCACCGAAUAGUUGGUUUACCUCUUUAAGGUAUAUUUGAUGUAUUUGUGAGUUUUUUCAACUUUCUACUUUGACUUGCGAGAAAUAAAGAACUCAUACUCAGAAUUUAUUUGGCUACCUUUACAAUGCUGCUAGUAAAAAAAAAAAAAACUAUGUUGCUUUAAAGACUUAGGCAAGAGAGGGGGAAGAGGAGAAAUGAAGGAAGGGGAGGUUAGGAAAGCAGAAAGGCGGGAAAGAGACAAAAGGGAAGGGAAGAGAGAAGAAAGGAAAAGGAAAUCCCAAAGAAAGCCUUUGCCUUUUCCUAAUCCCCCAUAGCAAGCAAUUAUUAUCAGCAUUUUCUGCCUGGAGGCAUUGGUAUGUAACAUAAAUCACAGAAUGGCUGUACUCAGCCAGGAACUGAGUGACUCAGGGAGAACUCCAAGUGGUGGGGACAAGCCAGCCCUACCUCCAGCAGGAGGGCUGCAUACACAGCUGGAUCCCUGAGUGUUCCUUAUUACACUUCCUGGUGACUCAGACAAGCACUCACAUGCUAGGGCAAGGGGUAUUUCAUUAGAGAGCGUUCAGGUGAUUUUUCAUCCUCUAAAGCUGAGAUGGAGCUGAGUCAGCCAAUAUAAAUCCAGAUACCUAAUUAAAAGAGCUCAUUUGUAUCUGCUUGGCUGCUUGUGUGUGAAGGCUCAUAGAUUGUCUAAGCUGAAGUUUCUAUGAAAACUCCUGUGUUAGGAUACACUAGCUCUACCUGCUGAAAAAGACUCAGCCCCUUGGCUCCUUUGGUGGAACUGUGCUGCACCUUUAUCCAGGUGAACCAUGGUGUUUGGUGUGGAAAAUGUUGGCAGAAAAAGGAAGAUAGCUCAGAAAAGUAGAACGAAGGUGAUAAUUAUUUCAUCUUCAGAAUUUUCAGGAGCUAGAUAUCUUCUGCCACAACUCUUCCAACUUGAUAAGCAAAAUACCAAGGGGGUUCCAAAAGAAGCAGAGCUAAAGGAACACAUCUUCUCCUGAUUAUAUUUUCUUGCAUUAAUCUGUUCAAAAAUAUGAGUAGUUGAAAAGAGUUGCAUAAGGCAAAAAGCUUUGAUACUUUAUCUCUGCAAGAUGCAAAACAUCCUCUAAUAAAAAUAAUUUACCUCUCUAAUCCACCAAGAAGUAAAAUAAGAUUCCAGGGUGAAACAUAAAUCAUUUGUAAUUUCAGCCAGCCAGGUUCUAAAUGAGUUACCCUCUUAUUUGGACAUAGAAAUUUUAAUCUCUGGAGAUUUAUCAUUUGCAACUUUGCAGCUAUAAUUAUGUUUAAGGCACAUGUCUGUUCUUAACUAGAUAGGGAAUGUGUCACAGCCCUUUAUGUAUCGAAGGCAUCUGCCAUGAUGUCUAGCACAGCAUAAGCAUGGAGUCAGUGUUGAUUGGAAAUGAUAAAAAAAAAAACGAACAAACAAAACCCUUGUACUAGUUUAUGAAUAUUAUUCAUCUUUGCUUGGUUCCUUUCCUAAUGGCUAAGAAGCUGAAGACCUGUAUGUGUCUUAGAAACACGUGAGUCUUUAUCACUCUUCUCAGUUUAACAUUUAUGUCCCAAUGAUAUAAAUAGGGUUUGUGCUUUUUCUAUUCCUAAAGUGUUCUGAAUUUGAGUAUCUAAAAUAUGAACUUGAACACCCAAACUAAAUUUUCUUAACUUUUAUGCAGCAUACUUCACAAAAGUAAAGACUCUGAAUGUUCAAAUGUGACCAACAGGCUUGGAUUAAGUAAAAGCAAUUACAGAAGAUGACUAUUUUCUGUGAGUAAAUUACUAUAUUUCUAGUAGAAACUUUGACUUGGGGAUUAACUUCAAAGAGUGUUAAAACUAAAAAGGACUUAGGAAUUAUCAAGCCCCAUUUUUAAAAAACUUUUUAAUUUUUUUUUUUUUUUCAAAAUUUUAUACUACAGAAACCCUUGGAAACUGACAUUCAAGCUUUGUAGAUAGAGCAAAUAUGUUAAGUGUUCCUCUGGUUUAGAAAACAGGUUGGAUAUCUCACAUUCCAUCUCAUAUUCCACCUCUCAUAUUCCACUUCUUGUGGUGUUACAUGAAACAUCUAGGGAUCACAAGAGUCUAGUGGGAGACCCACUGCUCUUUACUUUACAAAGGAGGAAACUGAGGAUUAAAAUGUUACAAUGACUUGCCUAUACCAAAGAGCUAGCUUGUAUCAGAAGUGAAGAUAAAACCCAGACCUUCCCUGUUUUGCUUCCAUAAUAAAGCUGCCUUCACUCCUUUCUUUAUUUAAAAAGUAAAAUAUAUUCAUUGUAGAUAAUACCACAUUAAAUGUAUGGCAUCUAACUCCCAGUAGAAUUUUCUUUCCACUGUACCAUGCUGCUGCACUCUAGGUUCACUAGAAUAAAUACCAUUCACUCUGUGUGUGUGUGUGUGUGUGUGUGGGUGUGUGUGUGUGUGUGUGUGUGUAGCUACUAUAUAGUGCCAAACUUCAAGCUGAAGGGAAUUCAAACCACAAGUCAUGGUCUUUUAAUUUUUUGGAGUGAAUGAUUCAAUGGCAAAAAUGUAUAAAAAUAAGUUAAGUAGAAAGGGGAAAGUAUGCCCCCAUGUAACUGGAAAACACAAGGGUGUUUAAUUUCAGGCAUGAUUGAAUCUGGAAGUUCAAAUGACGUCAUAAGAAUUAUGUUUUUCUCUCUACCUAAGUGCUUCUGCAUACAAUGGGAAAGAUGACCCUGGAAAUUCCAGACUAGAUAAUAUAUGAGAUCUCAGAAGAAAAAAGAGCCAACCUCUCUCCUCUGUCUUUCCCCCUUUCCUUCUCUCUUCCUCUUUUUUCAGCCAUUUCAGUUUGUUGAAAGAAAUAAUCUGACUGGCUCUGAUUUAGUCAAUGCUCACUCAUUAGCCAAGUACUCUUUCUAAGGGACAUAGUAAUCUGAUUGACUAGUUUGAUGACCAAUGCCAUAUCAAGGGAGGUCAAGUUGUAUGACAAAAAGCCACACCAAGUGACUACAAUUCUUUGAAGAAAAGAUGCUACGCAGAUAAAAGUGAAAGACAACUCUACAUGAAGAUAAUUUCCAGAUGUAUGUAUGGCUAAAAAUGCCAAAAUAGGAUUUUACCUACUAUAGUUCUUUUUACCUAUAAUCUAAUACCUGGUUGAUCAGUCUUGUUUCUCUCCUGUUUCAUCUUUACUUUUUUGGUAAAUGUGCCACUAAGCAAAGCAAUAUCCAAAGUGAGAGUUUUUAGGAACCAGUGGCUCCACAACAACCACAAAUAGGAUAGUUUGUCAAAGGAUCUUGACAUUCAGUGGAAAAGCUGUUAAGAAGAGGUCACAGCAGUUGCCACAGACAAGGUCAGGCUUUGGGUAAAUGAUAUAUGCAAACCUCAUAAAGGAUCCACCCACAAUUCUUCAUAGCUUAAUUUUACUAUACAUUCCUUUGUAUUGCACACCAGGCCAUUUUUUUUGUGUCAUUCUCUUUAUGAAUGCCACAUCUGAGAUACCACUCAGUACAUACUAGCUAGUCACUAAAAAUUUACUUAGUGAAUCUGCAAAUCAAUGAAUAAUAACUUCUCAGAUGGUAUUGUAUCUAGAUCCCACUGUCUUGAUGAGGAUUUGUUUCUUGGUUACUUUUUCUCCCAUAACAGGAAAGAAAGGUUUAUUGUGAGCACUAGGUAUCUCUGGGGGAUGAAGAAGACAUUAACAGCAAAGAAAACACAGAAAAUGGAGAGAAGUGUUGCUAAAAUCAUAUUUCAUGAAGUUGCCUCUCUAAACUUAAAGAUGCCUUUGUUAUUAAAAAUAAGCGUUAUGCUCAGAGAGUUAAUUAGAACUAGUCUUUUUCCCAGAAUGUGUUUCUGACUAUAUGGUUGUAUAAUAUUCUGUGCUUUCUACUUUCUACUAAUAAUAAGUACCAUUAUGACAUAUCUGGGUUACUUAGGCCAAUUUCUCUGUCCGAAUCAUAUAUUUAGUUUUGGUUUCUAUUCCUAAAUUAGCUAGGUAGGUCUGUACCAGAUUUCACUUUAGCCCAGACUAGUUCAACAUUUAUAUUUGAUCACAGAAGAGAAUGGACAGGAGUGUGGAUAACUUAGUUUGAUUCAUCCCUAAUAUGAGAAAGAUGUGGCCUAGUGACAAUAGUUCAGGAAAGCAGACCAUCUUUGUGUUAGUAUCCAGAACAUUAUGCAUACUAACUGUUAUGACAUGGUAAUUCUGUUCCCGAGUUUAUAGUCUUUCAUGUAGCAGAUAUACAUUCUAGGAUGAAAGUAAAUAAAUAAAUAAAUAAUACAUGAAUAAAUAAAAUUAAUAUCAGAGUGGGGACUGAAACCCAUGUCUUUCCUUAUUAUCAUGGCAUUAGAAACUUGCCUUUAUUUUAUAAGAGGCAAGCCUCCAGGCUUAAUGAAGCUGCUCCCUCAAUAGUCGUGUGAAUCAGAAGAGCUGGGGGAAAAAAAAAGCAGGGAUCCUUUUCCAUCUUUUGCUUAGUUAUAAUGCUAGUUAUACUCCAAGUGCAAACUCUUUGAAAAUAGUGAUGAUGUAGGAACAGGCAGAAUUUUAGAACCCACAUGGAAUUUGCAACCUUAGCUUGAAAAAUCCUCUCUUGACAUAUAGACUAUGCAGAUUUGCUAUAUAAGUGAUUUACAAAGAAAGCAUAUGGAAUUCACUGUCACUUUUCUCCAAUCACUCUUCACUUCUUCCACAUAUAUUUGAAGGAUUACGAAAAUGACUGAUCCUGGAAUAGGUCCCAGGGUGAGCCAGGACCAGGAAACAUGGUUUGCAAUGAGUUCCAAAGAGCCUUAUUCUUCUCCAUUAGGUUACUUGUGAGUAGAGGGCAUUGUCAAAUGUAGUCAUUUUCAUUUUUGUGUGAGGCAGGGCAGUGUCUUCCAAAGGCUGGGCAGGGGGACCUAACCCUUCAAGUCUUACUUCUAGAGAAAACUUACCUACGUCAUUCUAAAUAGACUCCUCAAAUCCUCACAUUCAUUUCUAAUUAUUAAACUACCAAAUAAGGUUAAAUAUGCACACAGUUUAUGUGUUUCUGUUAUGGCAAUGACCACAACUCACUGUGCUUGUUUCCAGGUCACUCUUGCCCACUUUUGGCUUCAGGUGGCAUGUUACUAUCACGGUAUCCCUAGUGUACCACUGUGCAUGACAAAUAGCGCAUGUCAGUAACCAUGCAGUAACCACCAUCAGUUUUGAAUUUUAUUCAAAGGGCUUUCACAUAGGCAAUCUCUUUUUAUAACACAUUUCCAUAGCAUAUCAAGAGCCAAUUUUUUAAAUCUCUGAGUAACACACAGAAAAAUUGAGGUGUGAUAAUGUGUAUUUGCACAGCAAAUCAGGGACAAAAUAGGGUGUUUGCCUGAAUUCCAAGCCCAACAUCUUUGUACUACUUUCUUAUGUCACCUAUACUCAGACUUCAGAAUAGAUGUGCUACAUUCUUAUAUCAGCUGUAUUCAGACUUCAGAAUACAUUUUCAUGUACCUGGAACAUGGAAAAUAGAAUAGAGAAUAAGAAAAAAGACAAACUUUCCAAAACACCAAACCCUAGAAAUGAGUACCCCAAACACAGGGCACUUUUGUUCUUCAAUCUUGCAGCAGAACAUAACCACGUGGUGAUAAAUGUGACUGUAAAUGUCAGACCGUGUUGCUAAUUUUUCAGUCAAGGAUAGAAAAAUGAUUUUAGUCUUCCAAAUAUUUAAUACAUUUUUUUGCAAAAAUUAUGUUUUUACUUUUUAUAUUUAGUGCAUGUAAUCAUUUGUAUAUUUAUUAAAUCUUUAUUCUAUUCAGUGUUGAUUAUAAGUAAUAUAAAAUGGCUUGAAGGUGUUGGUGGAGGAGUGAAGCCCUUUUCUCUCGGGCUACUUUGAUUCACCUGUGAGAGACCAUGAAUAGGACCAAUUUCACUGGCUGAAACCUAGAAGAUGUCUGUAGGAGCCCAUGCUUAGAUCUUCACAUUUCACCCCUGCUUUAUUCUCUGGGCUAAGUAUGUCUGAGGUAGGCAGAAUAAUGCCCCCACGCUGGAGAUGUUUACUCCUUAUCCUGGGAAUCUGUGACUAUGUUACCUUGAAAGGCAAAAAGGGCUCCACAGAUAUGAUUAAAUUAACGACUUGAGAUGAAGAGAUUAUCCUGGAUUAUCUAAAUUGGCCCAGUGUAAUCACAAGGAUCCUUAAAAGAAUCAGAGAAGGAGAAGUGAUGACAAAAACAUAGCUUCAGAGUCAAAAUCAAAAAGAGAUUAUUGAUGCUGCACUGCUGGCUUUGAAGAUGGAAGGUGGCCAGGAGCUCAGGAAUGCAGAGAGCCUUUAAACUGGAGAAGGCAAGGAAUUGAUUCCUUCUUCAGCCUCAAGAAGGACCAUAGCCAUGCCACGACUUUGCUUUUAGCCCAGUGAGGCCCAUUUUGGACAUCUGAUCUCUAAAACUGUAAGAUAAUAUGUUUGAGCUGCCUUAAAUUUCCAAGUUUGAGUUAAUUGACUAUAACUGAAAUAGGAAAGUAAUAUGGUAUUUAAAAACAAAGUGUUAAAUGUAUAGAACUAAAAGGAAAACAGAUUUACCAAUUUCCUGUAUUCUAAAAUCCUCCAGUCCACCUAUCACCUCAUUAUUAGAGCUGCCUUUCAAAGACACAGCACUGACUAUUACUCUCCCACGCAAAAAGACUUGAAUGGCUCAACAUUACCUACUGAAUAUAAUACCACACUUCAGCCUGACAUUCAUCUUUCCCACGAACUUCCUUACAUUCUGUCUCUCAUUUACUUACAUUUUUCAUGUUUCAGUCGUAUCAAACUACUUGUCAAUCUCUGAAAACUCAUUUAAGUUUGCCACCUUUGAACCUGUGCCCAAAGCAUUCCUUAGCCUACAAUUUCCUCUUCACCCCUUCUAUACAUUUUCAUUCAACUUACUUGUCCCUAAGGUCCAGUAUAAUGCUAUAUCCUCAAAGAGACGUUUGCACAAUUCAUAAAUUACCUUUCCUUCCUCAAAACUCUUUUAGCUUGUUGUUUUUAUUCCAUGGUGUCACCCAUUUCAUUGUGCCAUGGUUGCCUAUAUUCCUGUCUCACUUCCUGGAUUGUAAGAACACUGAGGGCAGGAAAGAAGGAUGAGGAAAUUGCCUGUUUUUCCCUGAAGUACCUUGAGCUAGAAGCUCAAUAACCAUGAUUUAAUUGAAUUGAAAAGCUGACACUAAGCAUUCAUUGCUGACACUAAGCAUUCAUUUCUGACACUAAGCAGAGAGGAUUUUAUUCAUAAUCAUCAUCUAUCAGUCACAGCAUCCUUGUAGUCAGGGCUGUGGAUCUGAGAUAUGGUUCUCAGUUUUACUGUUGAGAUCCAUAUUUCCAUAUUUCAAGUGUGAAAUAAGAAUUUCUACUUUGGGUGACAGUAAACAUCAGGUGAUGGCUGGUGCCACUGGGCUUAAGAGUGAACAUCCUCUCUUCCUCCCCACUAAGAGCAGGCUGACUUAUAAAUAGAGACAUUUUACCCAGAUUUUAUUUCCAGUGGUUUCACUCUGCAUUCCACUAUGCACCAUUUAAUGAAACCAAGUUUUGCUUCAGAACUGGUUGAUUCUCUGCACCAGGUUAGAGAGUCCAGGGAGCAUGUACAAUCAAAUUCCGUCCAACUAAGCAAUGAGAUGUGAAAUUGGUCUGGGAGCACACGAGCACCUUGAACGAUGUCACACUGACUUGUUUGCUACCAGAAUGGAUGAGUGCAGGCCCUCUCUGAAAGAAGUUUCCUGGGUAAUUGAGCCCAAAUGCCUGGGAACUAGUAGCUAGCAGGUAAAUAAUUUCUUCUCAACAGAGGUUAAACACAAGAAUGCUUUGUCUUGUUUGGCCCAUCAUCCUUUAAAUUUGAACUUCUUAGCCUCACGGGGACGGUGCUUACCUACCAGAGACCUAGAGGCAUUAAAGCCAGUCCGGAGUUUCCAGGAAGGAAGAAAUCCUUAUAGUACAUUUAUAUUAAAAAUAUAAAUUUUAUACGAUUGUCUUCUUCGUUUAAAAUACAUACUUAUUUGUGAAAGCUACAACCCAAGAGAUUUAAUAGAAUAAAGGGGAAACUGAAAAACACAUACAACGUUUCUUCUGACUCUUUUCUUCUAAAUUUUGAGUUGGGGUGUUCAUCCCCUACCCCUUUCUCUGUCUCUCUCUUCUUCUCCUGUUGCUGCUGUUCCACCUCUUCUUUAUCAUCCACUUCUACUUCUGUCCUCCUCCUUCCUUUUCUCCUCCUUUCUUUUCAUUGCUGACACUAACCAGAGAGGAUUUUAUUCAUGAUCAUCAUCUAUCAGUCACAGCAUCCUUGUGAAGCAUUCAUUGUUGGCCCUCUGUCUACAGUGCUGAAGUACUUGGAUCACUGGCCAGCCCAAAAAUGGCAAGUUUCAGGUCAUGGCUCUUCUCCCUACUAUACAAUUUUCUACAUUUAAAUUUUACCUUUCUCUAUGUUCUUUCUUACUUCACAUCUUAGCACUUCUUGCUUUGCUCAACAUUUAAAGAAUAAUACAGGAUACAAAGAAGUUCUGAAGCAGUUGGUGGUGGUAUGACAGCUGUUCCACUAGUAUUCCCCCAGAGAGCAAUUUUACUCCAUCCGCAGAGGAAAAUUAAAUCACCCCCUCCCCAGCCCCCUGCACCAUUUCACCGAUGAGCACCUGCCAGUGACUUCCAACUGGUAGCCAUGACAAGAGAGGCCCUCAUCGCUUUCUGGGUGGGCAGCCAAAGUACAAAUGACAUCCCUGUGCCUCUGCUGACAGCCAGAUCUGGUCAAGAAGCCAUUGCUCAAAACUUUCUACUUUCUGUAAAGAGGGGUCUGGAUUCUGUCUGCCCAAAGCUAGUGGGUAAGAAAGCUAGGGUGAUGGCUUUAGGGAUUGCCCCUUGAUUUUUCACAUCCUGAUAUCUCUCCAAAGUAAGGGUUGUUGGAGCUGGAAGGUGACAUUCUUUAAACAAACAACAACAACAAUAAUAAAGGAUUCCCAAAGAAAAAUUCAAUCAUUUGGAGGAGAGAAUGCUGCUGCCUUUCCUAGCCAGUUCUGCAUUUUCAAAGGGAGAUUUGUGCUGCAAGAAGCAGCUUUUGGAAGUCAUCUCAGGAGAAGAUUCUCUUUUUUUCCCUCACUAAUCAACCCUUUUGUGCUGGCUGGGUCCAGUGACGAGUCACAUGGAACCUGCAGGAAAGCUAUUUUAAACCUAUGUUUUGCAUGCCAAAUGUACGGGAGGCUAAAACCUGACAAGGGAGGUCACCGUCAUUCACCUUGCUGCUCCUGGGCCGGCCUUGAUGAUUCACAACUUUUAGCUGUGCCAGUCCCACCAAAGAUCUCCAAUAUCUCCUCGGAUGUCACUGUGAAUGAGGGCAGCAACGUGACUCUGGUCUGCAUGGCCAAUGGCCGUCCUGAACCUGUUAUCACCUGGAGACACCUUACACCAACUGGAAGGGAAUUUGAAGGAGAAGAAGAAUAUCUGGAGAUCCUUGGCAUCACCAGGGAGCAGUCAGGCAAAUAUGAGUGCAAAGCUGCCAACGAGGUCUCCUCGGCGGAUGUCAAACAAGUCAAGGUCACUGUGAACUAUCCUCCCACUAUCACAGAAUCCAAGAGCAAUGAAGCCACCACAGGACGACAAGCUUCACUCAAAUGUGAGGCCUCGGCAGUGCCUGCACCUGACUUUGAGUGGUACCGGGAUGACACUAGGAUAAAUAGUGCCAAUGGCCUUGAGAUUAAGAGCACGGAGGGCCAGUCUUCCCUGACGGUGACCAACGUCACUGAGGAGCACUACGGCAACUACACCUGUGUGGCUGCCAACAAGCUGGGGGUCACCAAUGCCAGCCUAGUCCUUUUCAAACGUGUUUUACCCACAAUCCCCCACCCCAUUCAAGAAAUUGGUACCACCGUGCACUUCAAGCAAAAAGGACCUGGGUCGGUGAGAGGAAUAAAUGGAUCCAUCAGUCUGGCCGUACCACUGUGGCUGCUGGCAGCAUCUCUGCUCUGCCUUCUCAGCAAAUGUUAAUAGAAUAAAAAUUUAAAAAUAAUUUAAAAAACACACAAAAAUGCGUCACACAGAAUACAGAGAGAGAGAGACAGAGAGAGAGAGAGAGAGAGAGAUGGGGGAGACCGUUUAUUUCACAACUUUGUGUGUUUAUACAUGAAGGGGGAAAUAAGAAAGUGAAGAAGAAAAUACAACAUUUAAAACAAUUUUACAGUCCAUCAUUAAAAAUUUAUGUAUCAUUCAGGAUGGAGAAGGUUCUACUGGGAUAUGUUUAUAUCUACUAAGCAAAUGUAUGCUGUGUAAAGACUACACCACACUAAGGACAUCUGGAUGCUGUAAAAAUAAGAGAAGAACCAGAUGGAUAUUAAGCCCCCCAACACACACUUUAUCCUUCCUUCCUUCAUCUUUUUUCAUCUGUGGGGAAGAAAAUAAGGUCUUGCCUUUGGUGUUUAUAUUUCCAUAACCUUUUAAUUCUAUUUUUCAUUUGAGCUGACUUGUAGCCACUUCAGACUAUCAAUGGAAUCUUAUGUUGAGCCUUUCUCUGGCUUUCCUUCCUCCACUAUCUCUCCAACUUUAGAGAUCAUCCCCUCUCCCUCCAGUGCGUUCUAUCUCCCCCACACCCACCCUAGAUACUCCCUUUUCACCCACCUUUCCUCCCUCACCUCUCCUCACCUCCACCCCCUCCCCAGAGCACUAGUCAUGCCGCAAAUGCUAGGAAGUGCCAUUUUCAUUUUCUCCACUGUGCGUGUGUGCUCAAGUCUUUCGCUCUCACGUGGGUGUACAUGUGUGUGAGCGUGUGUGUGUCUCUCUCUAAAGCAUGCCAAGGGAAUGGUCCAUGUGUACAUAGACUCAUUGUGCUGUAGAUACUGUCCUGCAUUGUAAUUGUGAGAUGCGGCUGUAACAAGUUGCUGGGGGAGAUGGCGGGGAAAGAGGCAAGGAGCAGAGUCCUCCCUACAUCCAUGGCUGUCACAUGGCAUCAGUGUGUAUUCAAACCAAGCUAUGCUCCUUCCAAGGGCAGGACCCCAUAUUCCUCCUAGUCCCAUCAUCAGAACCGAGUGGGGAGUCACUCAGAAUAUCACUGUAAAUGAAAGUGCCUACUAUCGAUGGGGUAAGCAAACAGCAUAAGGAAUUAUGACGUGGACGAGGUGACCUAGGAGAGAAAAUUUCAGAUUUUACUCUCAUUUCAUGAGUCUGAGGGAUUCUUAUAUUUCCUGGCAUUUAACAGGGUAGGCCCUGCUCCACUGUGAAAAUGAGCAGCAUGUGUUGAGUAAAUCCCCAGAAACAGGAAGGUCUCCAAGUGUCAACUCCCAGUGAAAGAAUGAUGAACCACUUGGAGAUCCUAAGCAGCCCUGUUUUACCUCCUCCCUAAUCUUAAAUAACAUUUGUCCCAUGAAUUCCCCUGAGCAGAGAUUGUUUCCUAUUUCAGAUAAAAUACAGUGAAAGUGAGCAAGGCAGAAAAAGUCAACAGAUGCCCAGGCUCCUACUGUAUUCUGGAGAUACUGUCAGAGCUCUAAUACAGAGCACUGGCCAUAAUGAAAAGCAGUUCACUCCUUGUGCUCCUCUGCAGAUGUUUUUCCCAGUGUUCUAGGUUAAUGUUUUAUUUGGUUGCCUGCAUAAUCCCUGUUCUGUUUCACUGAUGGUGUUUGCAGCACCACUGUUCAUGGUGGUCCACUGUUAUCCUAUGCCAGGGUGCUAAGAAUUGCAUGAUAUUCAUCUUCCCUGCUCUAUUUAAAUUUACAUCUAUAAGAGUCAUCUUGACAUUAACACUGAAAUGUGAUCUAGGUCCUUAACCAAAAUUGCUGGGCAACUUGUAAUAAAUUUAGACAGAAAUUUUAUGAGUACCACAAAGCUUGGUGUUACCACAUCACCAGAAGGAUUUCUUAGGAAAUGUCUUGCCGAGAGAGCUGGCUCUCUGCAUAUAGAUGUCUUUGUCAGAAAACCAACCCUUGCUCUCACUUACACAGUAGUAAGCACUGAAAGUGGUUCAGUUCAUGAGAGGACAGAGAAUUAUUUUGAGAUUAUAUUUGAAUGUAAUCUUGCAGAGCCAAAUAUGGUAUGUCAUUAAGUUGGAACCUUGUAAAUAGCUGUUCCAUGUUAUAAAAUGAGAAACUUUGUAACUGGAAAAAAAGAAAGGAAAGAAGGAAGGAAGGAAGGAAGGAAGGCAGGGAGGGGGGGACGGGGAAGGGGGGGAGGGAGGGAGGGAGGGAGGGAGGGAGGGAGGGAGGGAGGAAGGAAGGAAGGAAGGAAGGAAGGAGAAAGGAAAGGAAGGCAGGAGGGAGAAAGAUCUAAGUAGCAUUGUUAAUUUCUUCAAUUUCUUCUAAGGGAUUUUAUUGUUUGUUUUAGAAGCUUAUCACAGCCUUCUUUCAUGAUUUUGCAGUUUAGACUUGAUACAAGGAAAAAUUCAGCUUGGGGAUGGUUAAGAGUGUUUAUAGCAGAUUCUGACAUAGGAGAGAAAACAAAUUCUCAUCCAAGAAGGUAGCUAGUAAAAUAUAGGGAAGGUGAGCCAUAUUCCUAUGCAGCAUCAAUUUAUUGACAAUCAGGUAUUUCUCUUAACAGUUUGGUCUUCUUAGUUCAAGAAUAAAGGGUAUCAUCUUUAAUAAUAAGCAUUCCCCAAAAAUUGAAGAGGCAGUCACACACUUAAGUGUGUGGCUUUAGAAAAGCGCAUGCUAAUUUAAAGAUAUACAGGAAGAGAAAAGUAGGAGUUAAGUUGGAUGUUGUUAGAAGUUGGAUGUUAGUAUUACCUUCAGGAACAGAUCCCCAUGGCAUGUCACAGGCCUUAAUUAUAUACCUGGCUUUCUUAUUGUCUCCACUUUAUCAUGAGGACAAGGUCUUGGUUUCAUGGGAGGAACUUCUCCAUUGAAAUAAAUGUCUGCCAUGUCAGCACCGUUUGUUCCCUCAGUUUUAAUAUAAUGGACCAUAUAUUAAACAUAAUUAAACAUAUAUUUAAAUGUGGUGUUUGCCUGUGUCUCUAGCAGGAUCUUGAAAUUUUAAAAAUUUGCUUCUGGUUCCUGUUUCAGAGAAAACAUUGUCCCCAGAAAUUUCAUAGGAUUGAAAGUGUUCCCUAAGCAGUGUGAACAAUGGAGGAAAAUAUAGUUUAGAGAAAAGUCAGGGAAAGGUAGGGCCAGAGGACUGACACCAAGAAAUCAUUGAAUCUCAACAUAAGACUUCUUGGAAUUUAGUUAAUCAUAUUGGAAUAAAUUCCUUCAAGAAUCUUGUCCCUUGGUAAUCAAAGUUUGAAACCCCGCACUGAAAAGCACCAACUGGUUGGAAAUAAUAUACUGAGAGGAGUGAAAUUCAUCAAUUAAUCUGAGUGGCUAAUAUAUUUAAUAUCCUUUGUAUACAAAGUAAAACUCCACCAUUCGUAAAAGGAAAUCCUUAGACCCAACUUUCAGUUAACAAAAACAGAAAUGACUUUGACCCAGGGUGCUUCCUGAAGAAUGAGAACUAUCCAGGGCUUUACAACUGCAGAAUUGUAAUUAUGCUCUGUGCAAUUGUUGAGCAAAGGUUUUGCCUUGCUGGAUAAAAAGUCUUGUUUGUUUCGAGACAUGAAAUCCCCAUGUCUUAAAAGAACUAAGGCUUAUAGAAAAGCAGAUGGGUUUUCUCUCAGGAAGGACUGCCCCAUUGACCUUUGCCUUCUCUUCCAAGUCAGACAGACUUCUCGCUUGCCAUGGGCAUUUUUUUACUACAUAGUCAGACUACUGGGGCUACUUAUAGAGACCUUGUAAAAGUACUCGUGAUUUUCACGUUCUUGGAGGACCAAACAAAAAUCUGUUUCUCCUCCAAAAAUGGACUUACCUCCUUUGCACACAAAAGCUAAACUCCUCAGCAUGAAAUUGUUUGAGUUAUUACUUUACCAAGUUGUGAGCUUCUUGAAUCCUCCAGAGUCGCAGAUUCCAUCCCUGAGUUGGUUGUGGUUUCACUGUUUCUAUUGGCUAUUCUCCCUGAAUUUUUCAUUUUGUUCUUUGCAGGGCUCGAAUUAUUUGUGGAAAACAAUAAUAUAUAUGUGUGUGUAUUUUUUAUCUUUAUAGAUGCUAUAUUUACAAUAAUGUAUGUAUUAUAAGACAAAUUAAGAAUAAUGUUUUGAUCUUAAAAGGAAGAAAAGUACUGAAUUUGGUUGUUUAGAAAGAAAAUCUAUGCUCACGUAGAAAGACAUAGAGCCCCACUUUUUCCGUUUUGUAAUUAUUUGGCGAAAAGAAAUUUGCUUAUAGACUAUGUUUAAUGGGAUUAACCAUGUCCUCAUUUUUCUUUUCAUCCUCAUACACUUUUAGCCUGCAUUUAGUCUUGGUUACCAAUAUCAUUUUUUAAGAGAAAUGUAAGUACAGUGCUAUAUCUUACCUACAUAAACUAUUAAUAUUUUGAAGACAAAUGUGAAACACACCACAAAAAUGGUGAGAUAAGAAACAAAAAUGCAGUUUAGGAAGCCUCCUCCUUGCUUAAAUGUUUAGAAUAUUUCUUCUCCAAAGACUGCAUUUGCCUCAGUGAUGUAAAUUUUCCAUCAUGGUUGGCAUAAUAUCUGUAAACAUCUCACUAAAUGCAAAAUGGAGUUUACAUUUAUGUGCAUACUAGCAGAAAAGAAGUAAACUAUUCUCAUUUGCAUGUAGCUAUGCUGUUCAAAUGUCGCCAACCAAAAUUUAGGAAAGAAUUUGUUUUCACCCAGCAUGUACAUCUCACUUUUCUCUUGGCAAGGAAGCUGGUGUUAACGUUGGGUUUAGGUUUAACAUUUACACCAGCGAAAAUGUUUAUGAAUAUUAUGGAAAACUUAUUUUAAACCUUGAUUUCUUUUGAGCACAUUUACAUGCUGCGUGCUGAUUAAUAAAUUAGGCACCAAUCAUGUGUAAAUCAAUGUAAAUCACUAGUUUAUGUACAUAAUAUAAACUAUGUAAACUUCAUUUUUCAUGCAGUGCCCAACUACUGCUAAGGUUUACUAUGAUUCUUAAGGAAAAAAAAAUCAAAUAAAAAUAAAUAAAAACUGAAACGUUUCACAGUUCAGAAUCGGAAGAAUUACGACUAAAGCUCCAAAUAUGAGGUUGCCUUAGCCAAAGGAAGCAGACCCACAGGAACAGUUCAAGGUUUAUAUCCUGCUCAAGUCACCUCUUUGGUCUUUCAGGAUCUAAGUGGAGAUUGUCCCAACUGUUGCUGUAGUUGUCUCACCCGACCCCAAAGCAAGGGAAAUAGAGGGAAAGGUUUUAAGGGCUAUAUGUCUGCUGUAUCCACUCCCAGCUAUCUUCUUUUUACUCCUUUCUCACCAUCUAAGAUGUCUUAUUUAAAUAGCUCCAAGGAAGUGACCUAAACCUUGAUGAGCAAAAUAUUACUCAGUUUUUAUUUUCCAUUCAACAAAAGCAGUGGGAAAGCUUGCCAUCUGGAUUCUAAGAAAUUGUGCAAUAUAAAAAAUGUUAUAUCCUCGAGAAAUAUCUUGCUGAGUCACCCUAGGAAAUAACUACCUUUUAUUUAUCUGGUAGCCUAAUGUUUCCACACAUUUAUCCUGAAUAUUGCAAGUGAGGGACUGAAUCAUUUUUAAUUGGGAGUUAUCUUUCUCAGGCAUGUUCUCUUGGAGUCUUUUUGAAGUGCCUGACACGUGUAACAGGAUGACAUAUAUAUCAUUCCUACAAUAUGAACAACUGUUACAUAAAAAAUUAUCAAGGAGAUGAUUUCAGGAAACAAGUGAACUUUCUGCAAAGACUUAUAAAAAUUUUAGGUCAAAUUAACUUCAGGCUUUAAAUGCACUAAUCUACCUAAGAGAAAAAAAAAGAAAAAAAACAGGAAGGAGUUUUAAGGGCUCAUGUGCCUGUUGUAUCAACCCCCAAGUGUCUUCUUGGUACUGCUUCCUCAUCAUCUAAGAUAAACUGACAACUUUAAAGUGAGGUAGAAGGUGUAUUGAAUUGGGAGUCAGGAGAAUUGGGUUCUAACCCCAAGUUCAGCCACAAAUAAAGCUGUGAGACAUUGGCAAGUCAUUUAACUUUCCUGAGUCUUGGUUUUCUCAUCCUGAAAGUGAGGGAUUCGGCUGACGUCUCUAAAAUCUCUUUCAACUCUAACCUUUAUUCUGAAUAAGAAUUUAAUAUUCACUUAGUGCUGUGCCCAGCACUGUUUGUAAACAGCAGCUGUUUGUUAUCUCUAGUUUGGUCUCUGUAUUCUCAUCACUUCUCAGAACUAUCAUUCUACCGUCUUCAUUUCUAAACCCAAAACUGCUAGAAUACAGGGACUCUGGACUGGGUCUGUAAAUUUUUUCUGAUCAAAACUUUAUAGCAGUGUAGAGAAGGGACACAUUCAAAUUACACUAAGGACAUUGACAUAGCUGGGGUUGUUUCCUUGUUUAUAUUAUAAAACCUAAAUGUGGAACUAUAUUCUAAUAAUCUUUCAUAGGAAGGAAAAUAGCCAGACUGGGUAUUAUGCAUGUAACAAAUGAGGACAUUGUGCAUAAGAAAGGAAACAUUAGUUUUCUGUCAUCCUGGGCCAAGUACCUCAUUACAGUAAAUGUGUGUCUUUGGAAACUCUUUGCUUGUGCUGAUGGCGGUAAGCAUGGGGUCCCAGGCAGGUUCAAAGGCUGAACUGUAAGAAAUGGGCAAGACAAUACAUUUUGUUUUGGAAGGAAUUUCUCAUGGGAUAAGUUUCCCAAAGCUUGAAUUAUAGGCUAUGAAAUAAAGCAAAUAGAUGGAGAGAAAACAAGUAUUGUUUUCAAAAAGUACAAGUCAAUUCUAUUUAAAGAAGACAAGCUGAAAAUAAAACAAAAAUAAACACAAUUUAGGAGGUUACAGAGUUGAAGACAGUAUGAAUUGUUGUGAAGGCCAAAAUCAAAUGUGAAAGUUAGGUUCUCUGAGAAAAGGGUAAGCAGAAAGGAUGAUUUCUCAAGCAAUUAAUAAGGAAUUAUUUUCUUGUGCCAUGUUCUAGAUGCAUUGAGCACAGAUCCUCUUGUCCUAAGCUGUCCUAGAGGCUCAGGUUAGCAUCUAUCCAAAGUUGUCCUUUGAUUUUAUUGUCUGAAAGAACAGAAGGCAUCAGAGUUUCCAGUCACUGAAGAGUAGGGUUUGUUCAUCACUUCCCAGCAAUCACAUCACUUUGUGUAGGUAAGGAUAUAUGAUGUGCUUAGAUUACUUAUGAAGCUCUCUCUAAGUGGGAGAAUGACCUGUCCAUGGGACAACUCCCCGUUUUCAUGGUCAUUUCAGAAGUACCUCUUUUUGGGCAGUGCUCCUGGAUCUACUUCUACAGCCACAUUCUACUCUGCACAAUCCUCCCUAUGUAAAGCCAGGCACAGUACAAAUAUGCUUCUUGCAAGUGAAGAAAACCCAUGGAAGUCCUAGCUUCAUGGCACGCUGCAGCAAUCCCAAGCUACCAGGAGCCUCUUUUGAACCCACUUCCCUAAGUCUUUGCUCUUCACCAGAGAAUGGAAAUUGUUCAUCCUGGUGAACUGUGGCCAAGUUCUGCUCCCUAAGUAUUUACUUGGAGUAGGGAGGUUAAAGGGAAGAAAUUCAGGGGGAGAGAAGCAAAAGAGAACACUUCCAACUCCCUCCCCCAUCUCCCAAUGCUCCCCACCUUCCUUAUCACUGCUCUACUGAAGGGUGUAUAAAUCCUGCUCUUGGUUAGAAUUCUCCUUAUUAACAGUGUUAUAUACAUAUAAAUAUAUAUAUAAAUAUAUUCCUUUUUUCAGCCCUGUAGACAUGAACUGAUCUUCCCUUGAAGAUACAAACACAUGGCCAUUUUUUGUUUGGGAUUUUUUGUUUUUCAAGGUUUUUCAUUUUUGUUUAUUAGGUGGAUUUUUUUCCCUGGGUACUAGCUCUGUGAAGGAGAUAAAAAGCGCAAUGUGUGUUAAAAAAAAAAAAUUAAAAUUAAAAUGAAAAAAAGCUUUUUUUCUUUUCUUUUUAAAUGUAUUUAAAUUCUGUUUCUCUCUUCUGUUACUUUACACGUAUGAAUGCUCUGCUCUUCUGUGAUCUUAAAACAAAAUGAAAUAAACGUGAAAAGGAGAUGUGUCUUCA